ACCCCGCAAGCUGGACAGUGUCUGUCCAGAGCUGGUUCCCGAAGCGGGUGCUUGGGCCCGGGAGGUCAGGGGUCCCUUCACCACCUGCCCACUGCUGCCUGGCACUAUGCCCAGGACCAGCCUCCUUCUCCCUUUCCUGUUUCUCUCCUGAGGUGCUACAGGCCUGGCUGCCCCUUCCCCCAGGGAGCAGCUCAGAGCUCUCUGGUGACCUCUGGAGCUGUGAGCCGGUCACAUGCUGGGAUGGGUCAGCUCCUCUCCAACCGGUGGUCUGUAAUUGUUAUCCCCGGGUGUCAUUGUCCCCCCCUCCCCCGCCGUAUCUUUUGGAACAGCUGUGGUUAGGUCAAAGGAUCUGAAGGUAGACUACCUCCAGCCUUGGCUGCGCAAAAGCUGUAAAGCCUUAGGUUACUUACUGUGAGUCUCUGUUUCCUUAUCUAUCAAAUGGGAAUGAUCAUACCCUAGGAAUUUGUUGGGAGGAUCAGCUGAUACAAUGGAACUUGAUACAGAAAAGGGUUAACGCAUAGGGUUUUAAGCCAGAUAUUCAUUGACUCAUUCAGUACAUAAUUAUUGAGUGUAUUCUAUGGGGAGGUCCAGUGCUAAGCCUUGGAGAUUCAGUGGCACAGGUUCUACCUUAAUAGAAUUAAAAUCUAGCCCUUGACACUCAAGAGUUUAGUCCAUCUACUUUGGAGCUUGUUACAAGUGUAGCAGCUUAGGCCUGAGUCUAGCCCCGCAGAAUCAGAAUCUAAUUAUUCAUCCAUUUCCCCAGGUGAUUCAUGGGCACAUUACAGUUUGGGAAGCACUGGACUGGAUUAGAACUGGGGUUGUCUCCUGGCUCCACUGCUUACUGGUGAUCCCUUAAAAUCCCAGCCUAAGUUUUGUCAUUUGUAAAAUGGGUAGUUGUAAGGUCGAAAUGCAACAGAAGAUGCUUAAGAACACUUUUAGGGUGCAUGGCACGGGGGACUUAAUAAAUGGUGAAAUAUGCUAAUAACUGUGAGUGCUCUUGGGAAAAUGCAGAUGUCAGGGACUGCUGGGAUGAUGUUACAAGAGUUUAUCCUUUUUCUCCCUUGCUUGGAUGAGACCUUCAUUCCUGUUUCACCUGUUCUGUGUAGCAGGGCUGCGGAGGAGGCAGGUAGCUGGGGAAGUGAGAGAAGCAAAGGGACAGUUGCCUAUUGUGGGAGUGGCCUCUCUGCCUCAGGCUUGUGCUUAGUCAUCUCAGCCUCACAGCGUCCAGGUUACUGAUGGGGCAGAAUUUAUUGCCCCUGUUUUUAUAGAUGGGGAAACUGCUGCUCACGGGGUAGGAGGGAUGCUCCAGGACACAGAGCCGGCCAGGGCACCACCAGGAGAGGAACCCAGGCUCUUGACACUCUCCACAGUGCUCCUUCCCUUGAAGCACGCUGGUUGGGGAGGCAGAAGGAAAAGAAGAGCACGAUUUUGAAGAUCUCUCUGUGUCGGCACACCCAGCAACCAUAAAAAAGUACAAAACUGAACAGCAGGCUCUUCCAUUUAUUAGGAAAUCCACUUCCAGAGGAAGAUACUCCAUGGCCCCUUUCAGUAGCUCAUUGUCAACAAUGAGCAAAGAGUCUUAACUGAGCUUUGAGUUCCAAGAAUAAAUUUAAUUUGCCUGGGGACGCUGAGCAAGUCUCUUUGCCUCUCCUCGGUGCCUCAUGGUUACCCUCUGUACAAUGGAAUUAAUGAUAGGUUUCCUCCCCUUCCCUCUUGGGGAUGUGGUGAAAGUGAGACUGGAGAUGGUGGUGGUAUUAUGGGAGGAUUGUUCUGAAAUCACAGGGUGGCUUCUGUAGCGUCUUGGAGCAGAUGCAUGGCAGCGUGGGACAAAGGGACACAGGUGGCAGGUUCCAAGACUGAUCACUGUGCUUCUUUGCGUCACUUCUCUGCUUCUCAAUUCCUCCUUUAUACAACAAAGAAUUGAGUUGAUCUCAGAAGCCCCCUCUGGCGUUAUUAUAGGUUUUUCUUUGAAGACUGUUAAGGUUUAUGUGGAUUUUGGUGUCAGUUCACCUCCUCUUAUCCCCUCUCCCCAGCCAGACUCCCAGGGAUCACCCUCACUGAAACAAGAUAUGCGUCUUCUCCCUCUGAUUUCCGUUAUCAAUUAGAAGCGUUUGUUAACCUGCAUGAAACAAAUUGCACAUUGAGCAGCCUAUGCAAUCUCUUUCUGUGGUGUUCUUUCUAAAUCCUGGGGAGGGGAGGUGGUAACUGCCUCCCGAUAACUGGAGGGCUUUCCGUGCCUGUGAUUGACUUUGUUCUGGGUAGAUACAAAGAGAACAUGUGGGGUUGAUGGGUAGAAAUGAGGAAUCUGUAAGAAAGCGUUUUUAGUAGACAGAGCUGCCCAAGGAUGGAGUAGAUGGUGCACCCUCCAGCAUGGGAAGGAAGCAAGAAGCUUGUUGGGAUUUUGAAUGUUGUAGGAAUUUGAGCAUCUCUUGGAGGGGAGGUGAACUAGGAGAUAUAAGGCCUUCACCAACCUUAAGAAUGUGUGGUUUUAUAAAAUGCUUAAUUGUGAGCCUGUCCUGAGGCUUUGAAGUCUACAGGGACUGAGGCCUCAAGAGUUGCCCCUGUAAAGUGGCUCAUCACCCUUUUCCCAUAGGAUCAUUGUGAGGAUAAAAUGAGAUAAUCCGUGACAAUCACCCACCACUGUUAUUGUUAGUUCCUCUGUCUUGGCCUGCUGGCAACAGCGUCCACACAGAAGGGCAUCCCUUCCUGAGGCCAUGGUCACAAGAUCUGACUCACCUGGUCUCAUCUCAUCUCUUCUCUUGCACUGCUCUUCCUGGUGGGCUCCCUCGACAGCCUGCUUUUUCAGUGACACAGGACAGGCUUGCCAAGAAUGUGCAGUGCCUCUACCCAGCCUAUCCCAGGACAUGGUUUUCUCUGACUUCUCAGCAGCUGAACUUUGAAUCUGCUGAGUCCAGACAGUUCCAUGCUUUUGCAUGGCCCUGUUUUCAUUCAGCAAACAUUUGCUGAGUACUGAGUACCCACUGUGUGCCAGUCCUUGUACUAGAUGCUGGAGUGUAAUGGUGAUAAACGCAUGUUCCUGGCCCUUAGAAAGUUCAUGGUCAGGUAGGAAGAAACAGAAGAAAUAGACAUGAGGAUAUCAUCCUUGUGAUAGAAGCAACCACAGGAAGACCCUGUUGGCCAGUCUUUGGAAGAUGGGAGAUGGGCAUGAGGCUUUGGGUGGGUUCCCAAGAAGUAGUAAUGCUUGAGCUCAGCUGAUUCUUCCAGCCCAAUCUGACCUUUUCAGAUAUGUAAAGGUGGUUGGAGAUACAUAAGUUACUUUACGUACCAGAUAAGUAAAGAGACCUUGUAUCUAAUCCUCUCAACCCUGCAAAGCAGAGUGGGUUUUUCUAUUAUUCUCAUUCUGCAAGUGAGUGAAUUGAGGCUUAACAAGAAAGGCAAGGAUCCUAGAUUGUCUUAAUCACUCUCGCAUUGGUGUAUAAACCAUCAAGCAUAUAAACAACUCAAGGGAGCAUCAGCAGGGUCGCAUGUGCAUGGUACCUGCUGACCACCAUGAUCAGAGCUUUGUGACCUCUGUGUGCCUAGCAUCCUGCUGGGCGUCAAGUUUAGGCAGGAUUGACAAAGUCCUAGUAUCAAAGGGUAAAUGAUCACAUAGGGAAGACAAAGACAUGUAGUAUAUGACAAGAGGGCCAACAGUAAUCAAAGCCAUAUGGUGGUAAUGGAGAAGCCAGUGAUGUAUGGAAUAGAGGUUGAAGGCUUUGGACUCCCUUGGAGACGGAUCUGUAGAGGACUGGAAAUGACGUGGAUGUAAUGGCCCUUCAAAGACCAGCACUAAUAAGGACACACUAAUGAAAUCAACCACCUGGGGCUCUAAAGGCCAGACUAACUUUUUACUCUCUCUGUGUCUUGCUGCUUCCUAAAUGGCUGUUAUUGGCCUCCUUCCCCACUGGAAGCUCCAGGAUCUUUGUGGAAUCAUAGUUCCUUAGGAUAACAUUAUAACCCCAUCAGCAACAUGGAGCUGUGUACUUCUCCUUUAAAGCUUAAUUUGUUAAUAAAUAUUUAUCGAGCCGCUUUUAUGUGCCAGGUGCUUUGGAUCAUAACUGAACCUUAACAUACCAAUCUGCGCUUCACUGAGAUUCUGUCUUUCUCUAGUCAUAAAAUUUCAUUCAAGUCAGGAUUCCUGCCUCCCCUCUUCUCUGUACCUGGGAGGAUUCAUUCUCUGGAAGAGCUGUUUUUCUGUGAGCAGACGGGAACCAGAGCUGAGAGUGAUGGGGAUUGAGUAGGGAUUACAGCCCCAUCAGCCGGAGGCCAGAAAAUGCUUGGAUGAGAGAAGAGGAUUAAUUUUAUUUUUAUUCCUGUGAGUGUGGGGGAAGUCGGGGGAAUUGGCAGGAGCUAAGGGAGGGACACUUGUUCAUGUUGUCCUCUCUCUCUUCCAAAGCUUCCUCCCUGCCUUUUGUCAAAAUUUCUACCCAUCUUCCAAAACUCAUUUUUUAUAGGUAGUAGUGUUCUGUAACUGCAACUUAGAAUACUCUCCUCCAUUCUUGCAGCUCUCACGGGGUGCAUGUUGCUUUGCAGUAGGUUGUGGGUUUUUUUUUUUUGUUUGUUUGUUUUGUUUUUUUAAUUACCAUGGAGUGGGUUUGAAACCACUGUCCGUUGCUUUUUAUAAGUUAGACCCUUUAUCCCCUUUAUCUUCUAGGUCCUUUUGUCUUUAAGGUCAGUGUUUCUAGUACUUCUUGUCACCACAUCAAUUACAAUAACAACAAUCAUUUAUUGAGCAGCUACUAUUGGACAGACUUGUGCUACAUACCUUACAUACCUUGUCUCUAAUUCUCUCAACCCUGCAAAGCAAAGUGGGUUUUUAUAUUAUUCUCAUUUACAAGCAAGGAAUUGAGAUAUUAUUCUCGUUUUACAAGUGAAGGAAUUGAGUCUCAGGUUUGACUGAGAUCCCCAUCUGGGAAGUGGUGGGCUCAAGAAUUGAACGUGUGUGUCUUGCUUCUUCGUAUCCCCUUACACUGUAUUCGAUCAUCUCCCUAACUGCACUAUAUGCCUCUGAUGCAACAGCAGUUAUGAUAGUCCUCUGGAGCCCCAGGGCCUAGCACUCUGCAUGGUAAGCCUGUAUUAAACAUUUGUCUCUUAGUUGAUUAAUAACAGCUUGACCCUUACACAUCCUUUACUCAUUAUUAUGACUUAUUUUUCUUGCUCCAUUCCCUGUGGGCUGGUGAAUCUUUACCUACCUGAAGUGGAACAUUUACUGAGGGAAUCCAUAUGUUUGCUAAUGAAGCCAGACCUUACAGGUCCAUCCCCAAGGACGGAGUUCCAAGGCUCCUAACUACACCUAAACACCUAGCCCAAGAUGACAUGGAAGGUUGCCCCUAUUUAGAAAGACAAUGAAGGCGAAGAUGUGGCUACCAUGGUGAAAACUUAGGUACUCCAUUUUUCUCCUGGCAAAAUCCUACAUAUCUCCAAAGUCUCAGUUCCAGUGUCAUCCAGCUUCCCAGGCUGACAGCACUGAGCAUGCCUUUCCUCGGACCCCGCAAACUUUACUUUUGGUGGUGUAUACAAAUAGCCACAUGGUAUUGCAAUUUCAGAUGCCACUGGCUCUGUUAGUUCUUGUGCUCUGGGAGAGCACAGACCACAUAUGUCUCAUUCUCUCUUAUACCUUCCCAGCCCAAAGCCUGUAAAGCUGUAAACCAAACUGUCCUGUCAAUGAAUGGGGAUAUUCUGUAAAUUUAUUUGCCCGCAGAUUCUGUAGUCCCUGAGGGGCCUUACCUCCAGCCACCUUUAUGUUAGGCCCCUCUGCAACUGCCCCCACCCCAUCUCCUCUCUCAGGGUAGCCUGCUUUUUGGCAUUGGACCAUUUCCAUGGCAACUUUCCCCAGUCUCCAUCUGGAAACUGAGUGAAGUUCAACCCCCCACCUAAAGAGAUUAGUGGAGCAAAUACUGUCUGGUUAUGUUCAGCUGUCUGGGUUAGGACAGCUCAGUAUGGCAUCAGGGUUUUUUUUUUUUUAAUAAAUUUUUAAGUUUUAGCCUACUUUUAGAUUUAUGGAAAAGUUGCAAAGAUAGUACAGAGAGUUCCUGUCUAGUCCUCUCCUGGUUCCCUCACUUGGUCUCAUUUUAUACUACAGUGUACACUUAGCAAAACUAAGAGACUUAUAUUGGUACAUUACUAUUCACCCAACUCCAUACUUUAUUUGGAUUUCACUAGUUGUUCCACUAAUGUCCUCUUUCUGUUCUAGGAUGCGAUCCAGGACACCACAUUGCAUUCGGUUGUCACAUCUCCUUAGCUUCCUCUGGCCUGUCUGACAAUUGCUUAGUCUCUUGUUUUUUGUGACCUUGGCGGCAGGGCUCCGGCAUCUGUUUUCUAGUGCUCUGGAAGCACAUUUCCUGUGGCCAGUGCUACAUGCUACAGCUAGGGUGGUGGUGGAGCAGCCGUUAAGAGGCAACACUCCAGAUGGCUGAGGACAAAGUCCCGGCAGCCAGCUGCCCAGGCACCCCUCCUAGCUCAGGUGCCCACUGUCUGCAGGAUCUUGGUCAGGUUGCUUGGUGUCUUUAUGCAUUAGUUUUCUCAGCUGUAAGAUGGGGAAUAUCCCCAGAAGACUGGCCUAGGGAUUAACUGUCAUGGUCAAUAGAAAGCACACAUCUUAGAAGGAUCCUCACUCAGCACAUGUUGAGUGUUUAAUGAAGGUUGCGCGUUGUCACUGUUAUUUAAGUAUUCUAGAAUGACCAUGAGGGAGAGGAAGCUUGUGGGACAGAGGCUGAAAGGAGGGGUUGGGGAGAAGGCUGAGGAUGGAGUAAGACAGUAUUAGUUCCUUUCUUCCUCCUCUCUGUGUCCUUGAGAACUGAAUGCCAUGGUGGUGUCCAGAGGCCAGGACAGGAGACAGGGGAAGGGAGUGGAAGAGAGGGAAGAAGUGUGGGGUGGAGGAGGAAGGAUCUAAAGGACACCUGAGAUCUCCAGGAGGAAGAAGAAGGCCUUCUUUGAAUCUCCUUGAAUGGCUCCUGGGAUGAGAAAGAAAGCAGGAAGAAGGUCUGAUCUCCUCACCCUGAGUGGCCUUCUUGUAGGUUUCAUUUGGGUAAAUCCACACAUUCCACAAAAUUUCUCCAAGGAGUCACUUCUGCCAACAUUCUCUAAUAAGCUUCCAUCUUCCCCAGGCUCAACCUUGAAUUCAGGCAAGGUUGGGCACUGCGUCUUCUCUUGGGUGUGUAAUUCCUUGGGCUAAAGCACUGUCCUCACGUGUCAUGUGGUAUUGUAUCGCAUGGACUGUUGCUUGGCAGAUGUUAGAUGUGCAAUAAAUACUGCCGGAUGAAAGAAUGAACAAAUGAAUCUGUUACUUUGCAUGGAACAUUGUGGCUGUGCUGAUGGGUGAUGAGACCUUGAGAUGCCUCUCUGAGUUAAUGAAGGAGUGAACAUUGGAUUAGACCACCCAGGUUUCUAAUCUUGGCUGUGUUCCUUACUGUGUGAUUCUGGAUGAAUUAACCUUCCUAGCCACAGAUUCCUUGUUAGUGUACAUAACAUCUACCUAGAGGGCCUUUUCCCCCUCUUCUUCCUUUCUUGGGAGUUUUUGUCUUUCUUGUCUAGACCCACCUCAGGUCUGGAGAAGCAAAAGCAGGUAGGAUGGCAUGUGAGGAUUGGACUUCAAUGAUUUUUGUAUCCGACAAGCAGAAUGCAAGUUCUUUUGAAAUACGCAUAGAAGAUUAAGAAAUACCAUGUAUUAAGACACAAAGAAAAUGCCAAAUCUCACAGAAUAAAAGUCAUAUAGGCCGUUUCCUAACAGUGAUACAAUUAGAAAUUAAUACAAUAAUUGUCCUCCCCAGGCUAAUCCAUAUUGGAAAUGUAAGAACGCCUUUCUAAAUAACUCUUGGGCUAAAGAUAAAUCAAAGUAGAAAUGACAAACUAUUUAGAAAUAAAUGAUCGGCCGGGCGCGGUGGCUCAUGCCUAUAAUCCUAGCACUUUGGGAGGCCGAGGCAGGUGGAUCACCUGAGGUUGGGAGUUCAAGACCAUCCUGGCCAACAUGGCGGAAACCCUGUCUCUACUAAAAAUACAAAAUUAGCAGGGCAUGGUGGCGCAUGCCUGUAAUCCCAGCUACUUGGGAGACUGAGGCAGGAGAAUCACUUGAACCCGGGAGGUGGAGGUUGCAAUGAGCCAAGAUCAAGCCAUUGCACUCCAGCCUGGGCAACAAGAGCGAAACUCCGUCUCAAAAAAAAAAAAAUAAAAGGAAUGAUCACAAGAGCGGUAAAUAUCAAAAUUUGGGAGAAGUAGUGGAAGAAGAAUUGAGAGGGAGCUCUGUUUCUUUAAAAGCAUAUAGUAGAAAAAUGACAGAUUUAAAGCACAUGAGGUAAAUGCCAAUGAAUACAUGAAAUUCUCUCCUCCUGAGACAUCUAGUGUCACCAUCUAAGAAUUGGCAUUAGAAUUGCAUCUUUGCCAGAAACUCUUAGCAAAAACAAGGCCCAAUUUUCUGCUUUAGAUAACAUGAUCUUGGGCAUUUAAUAUGUGCCUAGCAUUGCUCUAAACAUGUCUCCUGUGGUACUGAUUUAAUCCUUGCAACAAUUCUAUGAGCAGAUUAUUCUUGUCAUGUCACAAAUGAAGAAACUGAGGCACAGAGAAGUUAAGUAAUCUGUUUAAGACCAUAUAGCUAUUAAAUGGUAGAGCCAGGUUUUCAACUCUGUAUCUCUGUAGAGGUACAGAGAUACAUCUGACUGCCUGAGUUGGAUUAUAUACACUGGUAUCUUUUUCACUCAUGCAUAUAGGUUAAUCCAACUUAGUUUUAUGGAUGUUGUGGUAUCCCCUGAAAUAAGCGAGAGCGUGUUCACUGAGCCUGAGUGGGGAGGAUGCCUUCAAGUGUGUGUAGUGGGGAACAGCAGAAGCCCUGGGCUCCCACAGACUUGCCUGUGAGUCCUAAUGAGGUCGUUUAUUAGCUGAAUCAUUUUGGAUGAAUUAUUUAAUUAAGCAGUUGUCUUAUCUGGAAAUGGGGAAAGUAAUAUUUGUCCCUCAGAGGGUUGAUGUGAGAAUUAAUACAUUUGAAACCACAAAAGUGCCUGCAACAACACACACACACAUUAUCUAUUAUUAUUAUUAUUAUUAUUAUUAUUAUUAUUAUUGUUAGGGCACACUGAGUGGAGUGGGGUCCUCAGGGACCUUGGCUCUUGUCCAGUUGUCCACUGGCUCACUGGCCUUGGGCUCACUGAUAGGAUUUAUUCUGCAGUGUCUUCAUCUUUCAAAUAGGGCUAAUUCUUUCCUCAAGUUGUUCAGCUAGGGCUUUCUUCAAAGUAAAAGCAUGAGGCUCACUUAGGAUAUCAUUAUCUGUCAAUCUCCUCUUGAUUUCAUCUGAUGAGUGUGUUGGGGAAGAUGGAAUUAAGUGAAAAGGGGAAGUGUGCCCUCUGGGAGGGUUUCACUGGAAGAGAAAUCACAGCUUAGUGAGAGAACUGGGCACUGGAGAAGAGUCAUUUGACUCUUCACAUAGGAAACAGAGAGCAUGGAGUGCCUGUUGAGAACCUACACUCAGAAUUUCUGGCUCUUUAAAGAAGAGGGACUGGAAAGACCAGAUGUUGGGCAGUGUGCACAUGGGUGUGUGUAUGUGUCUGUGUGUGUCUGUGUAACCUUUGUAAGUGGUGGUGUUUGUCUUUAGGAAUCCCCAGACCCUCAUUUGGAGGGAGGCAGUUGGGAGAAGUGGGUAGCAAGGACAAGAAAAACCAGGAGUCAGGCUGGGUGCGGUGGCUCAUGCGUGUAAUCCCAGCACUUUGGGAGACCGAGGAGGGUGGAUCACACAAGGUCAGGAGUCCAAGACCAGCCUGAGCUACAUGGUGAAACCCUGUCUCUACUAAAAAUAGAAAAAUUAGCUGGGUGUGGUGGUGUGCGCCUGUAAUCCCAGCUAUUUGGAAGGCUGAGGCAGGAGAAUCACUUGAACACAGGAGGCAGAGGCUGCAGUGAGCCGAGAUUGCACCACCGUACUCCAGCCUGGAAGAUAGAGCAAGACUCUGUCUCAAACAAACAAACAAACAAACAAAACAAACAAAACCCAGGUGUGUCAUUGUUUCUUUGAGUUAAAUUUAUUGGGAGAUAAUCUGGAUUUAUAAAGAAGCAUCUGUGUCUCCAGAGAAAUAAUUGUUUAAAUUUGGAGAAGAGAAGGUGCAAGAAUUUGUACUCGCUUGGUUGUGCCAGGAGGGGUGCUGCCCCACCGGCCCACAAAUCUUUAAUGCCCCACUGUGGGAAGUUAAGGACCAGAUAUACCCUUUCCCCUCUGUUAUUUCUUUGACCCAGAAACUUUCCUGGGGGCUCCUGGGCUUUCUGCCUUGUCCUGGGACCCUUUUGUCUGCCUGGGGUCUGGCACCUGUGGCAGGAAGAGAAUCAGAGCUGGUGAACACUGUGCUCUUCAUCUGGGAUGACUUCCUUUUUCUUUGUCUCAUUCUGCCUUGCUGCUCUGAUUUGUAAACAUUCUUAAGGAGAUACUGAUGAUUUAAACUUACGUUGCAGAUGUGUUUUAACUUGGAAAGGAGGGACAAACUCUUUUUAGAAAGCACUUGUUCAUCUAUUUCUGUGAUUUUCCAACUUUUUUUCUUUCUUUUGUGACAGUAGGACUCUUUCUUAAAAUGAAAUCUUAUAUUGAAUCCCAGUGUAUAAAGCAGAUAAAAGUAAAGCUCUGUAGAUUGAAGAGGGGGUGAGGCUCAGGACAGCUACGUCCCCCCAUUGGCUCCCCACUCCCUGAGUACCCUGAGUGGGGUUUCUGAGGCACAUGUGAAGUUUCCUGGGUUUCCGCAAAUCUGCACUGGAAAGCCAAGCCCCUCCUUAAUUGAUGAGAAAGGCUUAAUGGAAACAAAUGUUGUCCCCAAAGGGCCACAGCUCCACUUUCUCAGCCCAGGAUGCUUUCUGCAGGGUUGGGCUGCUUAGCUUCUGGGCCCCAGCUGCUCUCAGUGACAGGCUGCCCUGAGCAGCGUGCAGUGCGAUAAGAAGGGCUUAGGACAGAUGACUUAAGCUUGAGCCCUGUUUCGGCAAAUCAGUAGCUGGGAGACCUUGAAUAACUUACACCUUCUCUGACCUGCAUGUUCUCAACUACAUACUGCAGAUGGGAUUCGUUGACAUGGUGUACACAAAGCAGCUAGUGUCUUGUGGCCACCUAGCACCUACUAGGGGCUCUAUGGGGUUGCAAAUAUUUUUAUAAAUUAUAUGAGCUAAUGAAGAGAGGAACCUGUGGUCAGAUAGACUAACAAUGAUAGAGAAGGCAGUUGAGACAAAGACACUGAGCCUUGAGAGAGAGGAAUUGCAGUUCAGUUGCUUGAGGUUGCAUUCUGGGCCUCUGAACUCUUUCUACUUUCUGUCCAGAGAGGAGGUCAUAACCCUGGCUGUCCUUUCUGGAUUUGGGGGCACACUUGAGGGGUAGGGUCGGGGGAGAUAGAUCCCAGGUUGGAGUUCAGUGUUGCCUAAGUCAUUGGUGAUAUCUCUCAUCUCCUUGGGCGAGAGGCAUCUGGAGGUUGGGGAGGGGAGGAAGUUGAUGGCUGGGCUUGUGGUUCACUUGUGUUUUUUAUUGUGGCUGAUAUUGCAGCUACUGUAAUGUUCCUAUUACCAGAUAUGUUGAUUCUUUGAUAAAGAUGCUGAAGUUCUCUUCUUGGCUAAGCUCAGUCAUGUGGGCUGAAGAUAAGGGCAUUGUGUGCUUUCCUUGCCCUUGGGUUCUGAUGCCUCUAGAUCUGCAAGAGAGCACAUGUGUGUCAGAAGGGCAGGAGCCCUUACCCUGAGAUUGGUUGAGCUUGCUCUGUAGGGAAGCCUGCUGCUAGCUCCAGUUUCAUGUGACUCCAGAUAACAUGCGAUGAUGGCCUCUUCCUUGAGUUUUCUGAUCUGGACCAAACUUUGUUGUUGUUAUUUUGUAUUUUUGGAAGUGGCAUGCUACAGUGGGAAAAACUCUGCAUGGGAAAAUGGAAAUCCAGAAACCUGGGUUCUAUUCCUUUCUGUGUCAGUAACUCAUUAUUUCAUUUUGGGCCUUGGUUUCCCCCUGGUUUCUGUCCAGACCUCCUCUCUGGACAGAAAGUGAAAAGAGUUCAGGGACCCAGAAUUCAACCUCAACGUUUCCCUUUUUCUAAGUGAGGGGAUUUGAUGGUAAAAUCUUUAACAUUGCAUUCAGCUCUGAAAGUCCUGUAUCUAAAGAUACUCAUAUCCAGGUCAAAGCUGUAGAGAAGUUGACUUGGCCAGAUCUUAUGUAUGGUUGCUUUAUUGAGUUCUUACUGUGUGCUCUACAUUGCAUAGGGAACUUUAAAAUAUUAUCAUAUUGAAUUCUCACAGCAUCCCUGGCAGAUAGCAUAUAUUUUUUAUAGAAGAAGGAGGCAGGGAAGAGGGGUGGAUUUUGCAGGGAUUCUCUCUGUUGCAGUAAAACCAAAGAGUACGUUUUGGCAGUGCUGGUAGGCAUGCAGUCACAUUGCAUGUGACAGGCAGAUUCAGUCAGUUGAUAUCAACUUCAACUUUCUAGGUGCCCAGCCUUGUGUCAGGUGCCCAGGAGAUACUAGUAACACUUACGAGAUACUAUCCCUGACUUCAGGUUGGUUAAAAUUGAGCUUGAAGUUGAGACUGCAACUCAUUAAACUAUUUGAUAAACAUGAAGUGGGGCAAGUUUUGUGGGAGAAAUGGGCCCUGUGUUUGAAUAGCAGAGGAGUAUAUGAAUAUUGGUUGUGAUUGGGAAUAAGGGGACAUAGUGCUAAUAUGACUAUUGAUGGUGGUUGGGAAUGAGGGGGCAUGGUAUUAAGAAAGCCCAGGAGCAGGAAGCAAUGGGAUGUGUGCAGAAGACAUGAGGAGAUCAAGUUGAUGAGCAGAAGGUGUCUGGGGGAGAAUAGUGGGAAUAUAGCUAAACGCAUAAAUACGGUCAGCUUCCAAAGGGUUAUGACAGACAGGCUGAGGACUUUUAUACAGUAAGUAAUAGGGAACCAUCAUGUAUUGGGAAACAGGGACAUAAUGGGAUUGGACCAGAGAGAUAAUGGAGGUGGGUAUGGGCAGGAGACUGUUGUAAUGGUACAGGGUCUGCUACUCAAGCAAGGUCCAAAAAUACUCUAUUAUUACUAUUUUAUAGAUGAGGAAAUUGAGGCUCAGAGAUGUGUUACAUGUGUGUAACUUUACAGGGAGGUAGCAGUGUGGUUUUGUUACAUGGCUCUAUUGCAUAGUAGUGAGGUCUGGGCUUUUAGUGUAUCCAUCAUCCAAAUAGUAUACAUUGUAUCCAUUAAGUAAUUUCUUGUCAUCUACUCCCCUGCACACAUGUAUUGGGAAACAGGGACACAUACAUUUCUUUAUCCAAUCAUCCAUUGAUGGAUACUUAGGUUGAUUCCAUAUUUUUGAGGCUCAGAGGGGUUAAACCAUCUGUUUAAUGUUCAGUGAGUAGCAUGUGAUGGACCGUGGUAUAGAGCCCUGGCCAUUAUGUUGCCAUGGAGCCGAUCUUACUGACUUAGCCUUUAGUUUGAGAACUUCCUGUGGAGGAGGAGGAGGAGGAGGAGGAUGAGGAUGGGUGCGGACAGUGAUGACUCACAGGGGAUUCUGCUCAUGUAGACCCACAUCUUUUCAGCGGGGCAGCGGGGUUAGGCGCUGAUGUAUGCCUGGUAUUGUGCUUUCCAUAUGUGAUCUCGUUCAGUCCUCAUAAAGGUCAUAAGGUCUGUGGGGGUAUUACUACUUACAGGUUGGAAACUCAGAGAGGUUUGGGACUUGACUGAGGCAUCCCAGCCAGUAAUUGGAAACAGCAGGUUUUGGAUCUAGGUUUCUCUUUGCCCGUUUCACAGAUUCUCACUGAAGGCGACCAGGCUGCCUGGCUACAUCUGCACAAAGCUAAGAAGUAGCCAUUGUGGAUGUGGGGAAUCCCUGUGUGGAUACUAGGGGUCUCAAGAACUUACGUCAUGAUGGAGUGAUAAGUGUCUGCCUCCCAUGCUCCAGGUCACAGUUGUUCCCAGCUUCUGGAAACUUCCUUUAAUCCAUCCCAUGAUGAAGCAGCUGACACAGGAUGAUGAUACUGAUGCGGUUGAGAUUGCUAUCGACAACACGGCUUUUAUGGACGAGUUCUUUUCUGAGAUUGAGGAAACUCGGCUUAACAUUGACAAGAUCUCAGAACAUGUAGAGGAGGCUAAGAAACUCUACAGUAUCAUUCUCUCUGCACCGAUUCCAGAGCCAAAAACCAAGGAUGACCUAGAGCAGCUCACGACUGAGAUUAAGAAAAGGGCCAACAACGUCCGGAACAAACUGAAGAGCAUGGAGAAGCAUAUUGAAGAAGAUGAGGUCAGGUCAUCGGCAGACCUUCGGAUUCGGAAAUCCCAGCACUCUGUCCUUUCUCGGAAGUUUGUGGAGGUGAUGACCAAAUACAAUGAAGCUCAAGUGGACUUCCGAGAACGCAGCAAAGGGCGAAUCCAGCGGCAGCUCGAAAUUACUGGCAAAAAGACAACCGAUGAGGAGCUGGAGGAGAUGUUGGAGAGUGGCAACCCGGCCAUCUUCACUUCUGGGAUCAUUGACUCACAGAUUUCCAAGCAAGCCCUCAGUGAGAUUGAGGGACGACACAAGGACAUUGUGAGGCUGGAGAGCAGCAUCAAGGAGCUUCACGACAUGUUUAUGGACAUCGCCAUGCUGGUGGAGAAUCAGGGUGAGAUGUUAGAUAACAUAGAGUUGAAUGUCAUGCACACAGUGGACCACGUGGAGAAGGCACGAGAUGAAACGAAAAAAGCUGUGAAAUACCAGAGUCAGGCCCGGAAGAAGAAGAUCAUGAUCAUGAUCUGCUGUAUUAUCCUUGCGAUCAUCUUAGCUUCCACCAUUGGGAGCAUAUUUGCCUGAAAAAGGUGAGCCAUCUGUGGGGAGGGUCAGACCUUCUUUCACUGACUUGAAACCUUUGUGUCUUGGGGGCACUCUAGGUGCCUUAAUCUGGGUGGGAUUAGGUGCUAAUAAUGGUUAGAGAAAACUAAAGAAAGGGAUGUUUCAGAGACAGAAAAGUGAGUGAAGAAUGAACUGUUAGUAGGUAGUCUGUGGGAGGAGGGGGGAGACAGAAGGUGGCAAUCUGUCCUAUAACCUGGUGUGGCAGAAUGCUUUGUACAGGUGAAGGAUAGUGAUUCCUGCUAAACAGUUUGAGCCUUGGUAUCUGGAAGUGACAAAAAGAACAAGAAUUAGUUCUUGCAUUAGGUGCAUCUUGAACUUUUUGGAAGAGGGCCGGCCACACAGUAAAUUCAAAUUAAAUUUCUUCCCUUUCAAGGUUAAUGAAAGUUAACACAGCCUUGUAUGUAGUCCUUUACCCCGGGUAAGAGGGAUUUGGUGAUCCCAGCCACGAACACCAUGCUAUAUAAUCUAUGAUUUUUUUCCUCCAUUUUUCUGUUAUCUCCCACAGCCCUCACAGAUUGAUCGACUGGCAUUUCUAAUCCUCCUUCCACUUCUGUGGUACCAUCACUUCUCCACGCAGACUCCUCAUCAGCUUCUCCUCUUUCCAUUAUGAAACUUCUUAAGAAACAGGGCACCAAUCAACUACUUAUUAAGAAUUAUGCAAAGAAUAAACGUAUACAGAAUUGGGCGGAGGACAGGGACAGGGAGUACAGAUACAUAGCUGAUUAGGCAGAUGGUUUAAAGGAGGACUGCAGGGUAGAGAAGCAAGCAGAGUGGGCGCCUCUUUAGGAAGUGACACAGCCUGCAUGUGCAGUAUGGCUGUGAAGGGGCAGAUAUCAUAGCACACCUAACUCAACAGGAUCUUACUUGAACUGCUGUGAGUUGGUCAAGUCAGGGCACUUCUGCUCUUCAGGCUCCUCUAGGUCACACCUUUGACCACCCUACAUCUGUUUCCUCUUUCAGGCUCCAGUAGUAGUCUUAAAAGUGAAGUUUAUCUAAGGAUAAGCACAUGCCUAUCUUGCUCACUGCUGUGUCCCCACUUUUUAGCACAGCGCCUGCUGCUUACAGGUACUCAAAUAUCUGCUGACUUAAUUACUUAUAAUUAAGCUCUUAUUUCAGUCAUGGACAAAUCCUUGGGUUUGACUCCUAAACUCUUUAAGGUACCAAUGAGAACGUGGUUUGUUACUGUCAGAGGCUGUGUAAAGCCGCUUGGGAAUGGGCUGAUCUGCUUAUGCAAAAAUGCUACCAACCUUUCAAACCCCAUUACCACAACAUGAAAAUUUAAAGUGCUUUUUCUAUGGGUGGUGAUGGUGGAGUUCUAGCAACAGCCUCUUAAUCUGUGGAGAAGAUGGCUGGCUCCAGGACUGUGGUUCAAUAACGAAAUACAGGCCCACAAAAUAAAAUAGGUUUAUAGCAUGACUGAACUCACACAUCAGUAGAACACUCUGUGAACCAUAACAAAGAACAGAUAAAGGUGUCAAGUGAGAAAGGUGAAAUGAGGUUAUCACUCACUUCACCUCUCACCUGAUUUGUGUUGCUAGCUGAAACUGCUGGCCAGUAACGUAUGUAUAAGAAACUGUUAUAGGCCGGGCACGGUGGCUCAUGCCUGUAAUCACAGCACUUUGGGAGGCCAAGGCAGGUGGAUCACCAGACUGACCAACAUAGUGAAACCCCCUCUCUACAAAAAAUACAAAAAUUAGCCAGGCAUGGUGGCUUGCACCUGUAUUCCCAGCUACUUGGGAGGCUGAGGCAGGAGAAUUGCUUGAAUGCAAGAGGCGGAAGUUGCAGUGAGCCGAGAUCGCGCCACUGCACUCCAGCCUGGGCAACAAGAGCUAAAUUCCAUCUAAAAAAAAAAAAAAAACAAAAAAAAAAAACUGUUCUUAAUACUUAAUACUGUCCCCAAUUCCAUUCAAGGUUCAGUUGUGUUCAGCUUUAAAACCAGCUAUGUGAAUGUGAGUUCUAGUGCAGAUUAUUUAGUGAUUAUGUAACUAAAAUUGAUGAAAAAAUCACACUAUACAACUGUGAGGAGCACACAACUGCUAAGUUUGUACUUUUGAAAGUAAAUUAUUCUUUGUUUGAUACCUUAUUUUUUAAGAAAGUGGGAUUAAAAAUAUUUUGGUCAGUGCUGUUUUCUACCCACCUUCAAAAGCCAAUGGUUUGAUAUUUCUAUUAAUUUGUGCUUCCUUUAGUUUUAAUAGGGGAUAGAAGACUGCAGCUGGUUGGGUCUGGAAAACAUUAAUCUGGGCAAACGGAGCUGGAGCUAUGAGGAUCUGAGUCCUAGGGGGCCCUCAUUCACUAGCAGUAAGAAUUUAAGUGGUGCAUGGCACAUAGCACUGUACUAGAUUCUGCAGGGGCACAAACAUAGAGCCAAACACUCUCCCUCUUGGAGAAUUUCAGACCCAGAAAAGGCCACGCAGUUCUAACUUUUGUCAUCGGUUCCUUUUGCUAAAAGGCAAAGGGUAUGUUCCUUGCCUAUUGUCCAACAUACCCCUUCCAAGAUUGUGAGAAGAUGGGUAGCUGGGCAUCAAUAAAUAUUGAAUCAAUUGA